CCCUCACUCGUCCUCCGCGCGUCGCCGCUCUUCGGUUCUGCUCUGUCCGCCGCCAUGGCCCAGUGAGUGACUCGCCAGGGGCAGCCCGGCUCGGCCUCAGCGGGCGGGGAACUCUUUGGGGGUCGAGAUCUCCCUCGUUCUCUCCGACGCCUCCCACCCUGGGGGUCGCCUGAGCUCACUUGGGGCUCUGUGACCCUGGCCCUACGGCGUCUCGGGCCCAGAGCUCCUUCCCUGCGGGCCCGGCCCCCUGCCCUCUCGGCCGCGCAGAGCUGACAUCGCGCUGAUCGGAUUGGCCGUCAUGGGCCAGAACUUAAUUCUGAACAUGAAUGACCACGGCUUUGUGGUCUGUGCUUUUAAUAGGACUGUCUCCAAAGUUGAUGAUUUCUUGGCCAAUGAGGCAAAGGGAACCAAAGUGGUGGGUGCCCAGUCCCUGAAAGAGAUGGUCUCCAAGCUGAAGAAGCCCCGGCGGAUCAUCCUCCUGGUGAAGGCUGGGCAAGCUGUGGAUGAUUUCAUCGAGAAAUUGGUACCAUUGUUGGAUACUGGUGACAUCAUCAUUGACGGAGGAAAUUCUGAAUAUAGGGACACCACAAGACGGUGCCGAGACCUCAAGGCCAAGGGAAUUUUAUUUGUGGGGAGCGGAGUCAGUGGUGGAGAGGAAGGGGCCCGGUAUGGCCCAUCGCUCAUGCCAGGAGGGAACAAAGAAGCGUGGCCCCACAUCAAGACCAUCUUCCAAGGCAUUGCUGCAAAAGUGGGAACUGGAGAACCCUGCUGUGACUGGGUGGGAGAUGAGGGAGCAGGCCACUUCGUGAAGAUGGUGCACAACGGGAUAGAGUAUGGGGACAUGCAGCUGAUCUGUGAGGCAUACCACCUGAUGAAAGACGUGCUGGGCAUGGCGCAGGACGAGAUGGCCCAGGCCUUUGAGGAUUGGAAUAAGACAGAGCUAGACUCAUUCCUGAUUGAAAUCACAGCCAAUAUUCUCAAGUUCCAAGACACCGAUGGCAAACACCUGCUGCCAAAGAUCAGGGACAGCGCGGGGCAGAAGGGCACAGGGAAGUGGACCGCCAUCUCCGCCCUGGAAUACGGCGUACCCGUCACCCUCAUUGGAGAAGCUGUCUUUGCUCGGUGCUUAUCAUCUCUGAAGGAUGAGAGAAUUCAAGCUAGCAAAAAGCUGAAGGGUCCCCAGAAGUUCCAGUUUGAUGGUGAUAAGAAAUCAUUCCUGGAGGACAUUCGGAAGGCACUCUACGCUUCCAAGAUCAUCUCUUACGCUCAAGGCUUUAUGCUGCUAAGGCAGGCAGCCACCGAGUUUGGCUGGACUCUCAAUUAUGGUGGCAUCGCCCUGAUGUGGAGAGGGGGCUGCAUCAUUAGAAGUGUAUUCCUAGGAAAGAUAAAGGAUGCAUUUGAUCGAAACCCGGAACUUCAGAACCUCCUACUGGACGACUUCUUUAAGUCAGCUGUUGAAAACUGCCAGGACUCCUGGCGGCGGGCAGUCAGCACUGGGGUCCAGGCUGGCAUUCCCAUGCCCUGUUUUACCACUGCCCUCUCCUUCUAUGACGGGUACAGACAUGAGAUGCUUCCAGCCAGCCUCAUCCAGGCUCAGCGGGAUUACUUCGGGGCUCACACCUAUGAACUCUUGGCCAAACCAGGGCAGUUUAUCCACACCAACUGGACAGGCCAUGGUGGCACCGUGUCAUCCUCGUCAUACAAUGCCUGAUCAUGCUGCUCCUGUCACCCUCCACGAUUCCACAGACCAGGACAUUCCAUGUGCCUCAUGGCACUGCCACCUGGCCCUUUGCCCUAUUUUCUGUUCAGUUUUUUAAAAGUGUUGUAAGAGACUCCUGAGGAAGACACACAGUUUAUUUGUAAAGUAGCUCUGUGAGAGCCACCAUGCCCUCUGCCCUUGCCUCUUGGGACUGACCAGGAGCUGCUCAUGUGCGUGAGAGUGGGAACCAUCUCCUUGCGGCAGUGGCUUCCGCGUGCCCCGUGUGCUGGUGCGGUUCCCAUCACGCAGACAGGAAGGGUGUUUGCGCACUCUGAUCAACUGGAACCUCUGUAUCAUGCGGCUGAAUUCCCUUUUUCCUUUACUCAAUAAAAGCUACAUCAGACUGAUGCUCUUUCUCCAGAUUCUUAGUCUCACCUCGGCCACAUGGAGCCAUUAUCCCCAUUGGCAGAAAGAUUUUUCUUUAAAAAAAAAGACUAGAAUAACACAAGAAACCACAUUUAGGAUUAUGCUUCACUCAGAGGAGGCAGGCAGGGAGGACACACCAGGGGCUUUAAUACACUGGGCAUGUUUUCUUUCUCCAAUUGGGCAAUGGGUACAUGGACGUUCACUGUAACGUGCUUUUUCUUUCGUCUUUUUUUUUUUUUUUUUUUUUUUUGCUCCUGGCAAGCUGUGCGUGACAUUCUUUAUGGCUUUUUGUAUGUCAAAUACUUCAUACUAAACUUUCUAGAGAAUUAAACUUUAAUGAUGGGCUCA